GACUUCCUUGUUGUGAGCCCCGGCCCGGCAGUGUCCCGACUCGUAGCCCCGCUGUUCUUAAUCCGGGCCGCUAGCCUGAGUCUAGGUCGCAGCCGCAGCCCCACCCCGUCGGUCACCUUUUCAGCGCAGGUCCUUUCCCCGCACGCCCUGCGCUCCCUAACAUGCCCAACCCCAGCAGCACCUCCUCUCCCUACCCCCUCCCUGAGGAAAUUAGGAACCUGUUGGCAGAUGUUGAAACAUUUGUAGCAGAUAUACUGAAAGGAGAAAAUUUAUCCAAGAAAGCAAAGGAAAAGAGAGAAUCCCUUAUUAAGAAGAUAAAAGAUGUAAAGUCUAUCUAUCUUCAGGAAUUUCAAGACAAAGGUGAUGCAGAAGAUGGGGAAGAAUAUGAUGACCCUUUUGCUGGGCCUCCAGACACUAUUUCAUUAGCCUCAGAACGAUAUGAUAAAGACGAUGAAGCCCCCUCUGAUGGAGCCCAGUUUCCUCCAAUUGCAGCACAAGACCUUCCUUUUGUUCUAAAGGCUGGCUACCUUGAAAAACGCAGAAAAGAUCACAGCUUUCUGGGAUUUGAAUGGCAGAAACGGUGGUGUGCUCUCAGUAAAACGGUAUUCUAUUAUUAUGGAAGUGAUAAAGACAAACAACAGAAAGGUGAAUUUGCAAUAGAUGGCUACAGUGUCAGAAUGAAUAACACUCUAAGAAAGGAUGGAAAGAAAGAUUGCUGUUUUGAAAUCUCUGCUCCUGAUAAACGUAUAUAUCAGUUUACAGCAGCUUCUCCCAAAGAUGCUGAAGAAUGGGUACAGCAGCUGAAAUUUGUAUUGCAAGAUAUGGAAUCUGAUAUUAUUCCUGAGGAUUAUGAUGAGAGAGGAGAAUUAUAUGAUGAUGUUGAUCAUCCUCUACCAAUAAGCAAUCCACUAACAAGCAGUCAACCAAUAGAUGAUGAAAUUUAUGAAGAACUUCCAGAAGAAGAAGAGGACAGUGCUCCAGUGAAAGUGGAAGAACAAAGGAAGAUGAGUCAGGAUAGUGUCCAUCACACCUCAGGGGAUAAGAGCACUGAUUAUGCUAAUUUUUACCAGGGAUUGUGGGAUUGUACUGGAGCUUUUUCUGAUGAGUUGUCAUUUAAGCGUGGUGAUGUGAUUUACAUUCUUAGCAAGGAAUACAAUAGAUAUGGCUGGUGGGUAGGAGAAAUGAAGGGAGCCAUUGGCUUGGUGCCUAAAGCCUACAUAAUGGAGAUGUAUGAUAUUUGAGAGUCCUGGGUCUCCAGAGCUUACAGAGAGGAAAUUGGUAUGCAGCAUACAAACAAAAACAACACCAAAUCAUGACAAAGGCACAGUCUGAGGAGGAGAAAGAAAGAGGAGAUCAGGAAAAACUCUCCUUGCACUUGAAUUCAAUUGCAAAAUACAAACAUCAAAAAUGGCAAAGUGUGUGUCAGUGCGUAAGUUGGGGCGGGGGGGGCGGGGAUUUUUUUUUUCUUUGGCUCAUCUCAGCUGGCAGCCUUAUUCCGCUUCAGUAAAGACAAGGUACAGAAAUGUCCUUUGGGUGACAUUCAAAACUCGAUAUAAAUCCUCUGCUUUAUGAGACUGCAGUGCAAUAAAUUACUUAGCCUAAUUGUAGAUGUAAUGAAUUACCAUAAUUAGUCAUGGGCUACAUUAAAUUAAUCAGCAUGGUACAUUAUUUUGCUAAAUUACAUCUUUGCCUUCCAAAGCCACCAGUGCAGCAAUCAGUGUUUUUUGCAAGAGGGGAAUGAUGCUAUAAUGAGAAGCCUUUCUGCUCCUAGAACAGUGACAGGAUAUGAAUUUUGAUGGGAAGCAGGAAGGUUUGGAAACACUGGAGUUCCAACUUGUGCCUUAAGUGUCUUUGGUUGUUAAUGAUACCCCAGUCCUCCUGCAGGGGAGCAGUGGGCUGUAGCUUGCGAAGGCUGUGGAAGAUUCCCCUCACAGGGGAAGAAAAACACUUAGAUGGUGCUUUAAGGCAAAUAAUAUAGCUGAUACAACAAGUCACAAAGCAGUGGGGUGGCAGAAAGAUAAUGUCUUUGAAAAUAUUAAUAGAUUUAGAAUGUUCUUUUACAUUGGUUGAUGAGAUUUAUAGUUACCAGGUAUUUCUUUAUGAUUAUUAUUAUUAUUCAGACCGUUUGGAUCCAAGAUAAAGCCUGUAGCUAUUCUUGUUUUUUACUUAAACCUCCAGCUGUUCAAAAUCUUGCUUCUGCUUCUCAGUGGGUGAUCUGGAGGCAACCCACAUAUGAUCUAAAUAUUAUUCACUCUUCAGGAAAAUCUCGGGCAGCCGUGGGGUUCAUAGACUCAUAAUCUGGGAGUAUAGGUGCUUGCUUUUGUAGAAGGUCUUUUUUUUUUGCACUGGGGCCGGAGACACAUCCUGGUAGAUGAACCAUAGAAAGUAAGAGGUACUUCACCCAUAUUAACUCUUUGUAUGAAAUAUCUUUGUAAGUUCCACUCUUUCAAAAAGCAGUGCUCAUUCUCAAACCCAGUUACCUGCUCUUUACUGUCCUGUGUUGUUAUGAAAGAGUUUCUGCAAUAAGAUUCAUUGUCUUGAUUCCAGAAUAAGCUCUUUGGGGUUUGUAUAAUAUUUUUGAUAGUUUCUUGGUUUAUUUUAAGAGAAGAGCUGUAACUGAUCUGCACAUCUGUAUAACGGAGAUUCAAGAAAGGCUUUCAGAACAUAUCUGUGUUUUUGUUUGUACACUUGUCUGCUCAUACCAGAGGAAACCAAGUUAUUAUCAACUUGUUUGGAAACAGUAUAACAGUGGAAUGACACAGUGAACGACUAUGAUAUGAACACAAUCUUUAAAGAGUGGAAGUGAAUUAAAACCUAAUAUCCAAAAGAAAAAUACAAAUAAAGCUUGGUCACAGCUGUAGAAAAAUGCAUAGGGAUGCAGAAAAGUCCUGUAUUGUAAUUUGUGUUUUUGUCCUGGUGGGAAGCCAUUUAAUUAGUGCAAGAAGGUAUUGAAUUUUAGCUUAUCAUGCAUAUUGUUUUCCAGCUGUACUGAGGAUUGCCAAGUUUCUAAUGGCCUGACCCUGUUCUGUAAAUCAGCAGUAAAUUGCGGCAUUUACACUGAGCAAAGGCAAAGGGCUCAUUCUGUUGGGUUUGUGCUGUCACAGGAACCUGGGCUAAGGGAUUAAUAGGCUGAUGUUAAACAUCUGUCCCCUGUCUUUGGGGGGACGUAAACACACAAAGAGGGAAUCUAAUGCCAUCUACUAAAAGAUCUUCAAUGAGAGGAAGCCCUUGCUAACAUUUCCAUCCAGUGGCACCUUAGACACAUUGCCUCUUUAUGCUAAAACCCCACAGCACUAAGGGCCCUAUAAAUAGUCUCCAUGUGACAGCUCAGAGAAGAAGAGAGGUUUCCUCCAGACAUUAGUUGUGCUAAAAGAUUCAUCAUUACCUGCAGUCAUGAAAUAAAUCUUUGAUACUUACAACUAUAAUAUCCAUGCUCUACGUUUUAUUGCAGAUAUAGGUAGACAGUCAUUAUUUCUGACACUUUCUCAGCAUUACAAGGAGUACUCUAGGGGGAAAACUAGUGUACGGUGUUACAGAAAUAGAUUGAUAUAACCACAUAGAAACCAGUUACUUUACUGAGCCAUUGUAACCAAUACAAUAUUCCCUUAAUGACAUUAAACAGUCACCUAGAUUCCAAAUUCAGUGUAGGACUCCUAUCUAAAAACAACCUCAGUUAUCUACAAAUUAAGUUGCCAAGAGGGAAAUUUAUUUUUUUCAUCAUACAAUGGUUUACAAGAAAUAUAUUCCUGAAUGACAAUAAUUUUUUUUAGCAUUCAAGUUUAUUAUUAUUUAGGGGACAUUAAAACAAGACAAUGGUCAACAGCAAUCACUUUAUGGCACUUGUGGGGCAUUAGAAAUCAGUAUAUUGAGAAGCCUCCGCUUAAGAGGACUUGGAGUGGUUACUGUACAGUAGAUACUAGUGUCACAUAAAUUGCAAUAACAUGAUUUAUCAUACAGAAGAGGUGUUAAAGUUGUCUCUGGCCAUGAGCUAUUUAAGAGAGAGGCUUUUGCACAAUGUUUUUGAGCCCAGCAAGUGAGUUAUGGAAUCCUGUAAGAGUUCCUUCUUACCUGUAAGUCACUGCUUUUAGCAGUGGUGAUCUCCUCAAAACCCCUGAGCAAUAGUAGGCACAGGAUUUCAACCUUUAGUUACAUCACUUGUAACUGACUGCCACAUGCUUUACCACAGCAGCUCUAAGAGGCCAUCUGAUACACCUGGGGACCACCUGAUAUCACCAACGGGUCCCUGGAUCACUGAAUUCAACUAGUAGUCGCCACUUCUGAAAAGAGUUAUCAAUUCAAAAGGAAUCUUUGUGUUUGCAUAUUUAAAGCCAAGAUAAUUAUUGGUAGUGUCUGCAUAACAAAUGUAAUUUCAAUUAGACUGUUUUUCUCAAUUAAAAACUAUUGCUUGUGUGUAA